GCAGUUCCGGGGCGGCGCAUGACGCGACUGGGACUAGGCCGGAGGCAGCGGGGGACCGGCAGGUGGGCCGCUCAGUGCGUUGAAGGAUUCGAUCCCCAGUCCCUCCCUCCCAGUUCUAGGCGCCCCAAACCGCUCCAGGCCUGAGAGGUGGGCGGCCGCCUUAGUGGCUCCAGACUCUAGCUGGGGGCGGGGGGCCUCUGGCAACCUCGGUCUCUUCAAAGGCCCUUUGGGGUCUUCCGACUGUGUGGAAGGGGGAGCGGGGUCCGCACGGGUAGGACUGGGCCCCGCGGCCCCCAGGCCAGGAGCGUUUAAGUGCGCGUUCCCCUCCCCCGCCAAGGGUCCUGGCCCGGUUCGGGGGCGGAGGCAGCGGAGCCAGUCCCAGUGCCCAGUGCGGCAGCGGGCAGAGUGAGGAGGGUGCCUCUCCAGCCGCGCGCCCGCCCUGGGCCGCUAGCGAACCUUUGCGUCCUUCUGGCUCCAGGGAAAAGUUCGCUGUUUCUCCGCCUUUUGGCCAAGAUCAAGGAUAGUAUGGAGCGGGGACGAGGGGUGGGGGGCAAAGUUCGCGGGUCACUGGCAGAAAACGCCUCUGAUCGCGUGUUGCGUUUUUGUUGUUGUUGUUGUUUGAACUUCUGGAGCAUUCAGUGGUGCUGAUAACGCUCCUCAGUCCUCUGCUGGUAACCAUCAGGGCUAGGCGCUUCUCCUGCCUUGGGUCUCCUCCCCGCAUCUCAUCCCCUGUCUCCUGCAUUUGAUACACAGAUGGCAUUGUACUGUACAUUUCGUUGUAUUGCUUCUUUUUUUUUUUUAACAAAAGUUUAUUCUUAAAUGUACAACAGCUCCAAGACAACACUUAAUUCCAGCCAUAGGUGGCAAAAGAUGUUAUGGCAGGGAAUAGAGAGGUUUAAAUACUGAUGAAAUAAAGGGUCACCAUCUCCUUAGGCACAGGGAACAGCUUACUUUUUGCCAGAUUUCUUAAUUCCACUUGUGGCCAAGGGCCCCUUCCCCGUGGCCUUCCAUUUUAGCUCCUCGAGUUUCUUCUGCUCCUCUUUUUGUUUCUGCUUGAAAGCCUUAUCUUCCUCGUCCAUCUCCUUGGCCUGCAUUCUUGGGCUGUUUCAGUGGCUUCUUGCCACCUUCGUGGCCGGACAUGGCGCCUGCCGCCCCUUCCCCAGCAGUAUUGCUUCCUUUUUACCGGCUUGACAACAAGUUUGAAGCGGGGCUUUGCCAUAAAAUCCAGUUCCUUGCUCCCUGCUGUUGCCCACUGUUCCCAAGUGUGCAUCUACCACCUUCAGUGGACACGGACAGGCCACCUAGAGUCCCACUGCACCACUUGGUGAGAAUUUCCUUGAACAGUUAAUAUUGCUGAACCUUAUACCCCCAAUCUCAUGCUUAGUUCACUACCCAACUGGCAACAGCUCUUAAGACAGUCAAGAUUAUUCUCCCCACUUUACAGAUUAAAAAACUGAGGCACAGAAGGUUAAGUUAUUUGAACCAGGUCUGAUUUCAAAGCCUGUGUUCUCAACCAUUAGGUAAUCACUGGCUCUUCUAGUAAUUCAGUGACUCAAAAUACAGACUUGUACAUGUGUAAACACAAAAUUAUCAUGGGUUAAAGACCUUUAGGCUCACUUGCAAAUAUCGGGAAUCAUUUUAUCCAAAAAAGAAUGACAAGGAUCAGCAGAUUAAGCCUCUGCCCCUGCCAGAGGGCUCAAAGGGCAGGAAAAGGCAGUGAGAGAAGGAGAGACAGAAACCAAGAUGACAGUGCAGAGGAGGCAUGGGGAUGAGAUCACACACGGAGCCCUCACAGGGAAUGAGUUGGGGUCAUUUGAUGUUCAUAUUAGAAGCUGCAGGUUCUGCCUUCCACUGGGGCUGAUGGCACAAGAGCACUGUUACAUUUUACCUGCUGCCUUUGAGCUUGAGGUUGGGUGGUAAACCAUUCUUCACUGUUCUUAGCGGCUUUAUUUCUCAUAGAGUCAUGUGUUGCUUAACAACGGGGCUACAUUCUGAGAAAUGCAUCAUUAGGUGAUUGUGGUCAUUGUGGGAGCAUCACAGAGUGCACCUACACAGUCCUAGAUGGGGUAGCCUACUGCACACCAAGGCUACAUGGUGUAUAGCCUGUUGCUCCUAGAAUACAAACCUGGACAGCAUGGUACCGGGCUGAAUACUGUAGGCAACUGUAACACAAUGGUAAAUGUGUAUCUGAACAUAGAAAAGGCACAGUAAAAAUACAGUCUAAAAGAUUUUUUAAAUAGUACACCUGUACUGGGCAGUUACCAUAAAUGGAGCUUGCAGGACUGGAAGCUGCACUGGGUGAGUCAGCGAGUGAAUGGUGAGUGAAUGUGAAGGCCUAGGACAGCAGGGACUGGUUUGGCACCAGGGACUAUUUUCAUGAAAGACAGUUUUUCCAUGGACUUGCGGGCGGACAGAUGGUUUGGGGAUGAAACUGUUCCACCUCAGAUCAUCAGGCAUUAGAUUCUCAUAAGGAGCUCGCAACAACCUAGAUUCCUCACAUGCACAGUUCACAAUAGGGUUCGCACUCCUAUGAGAUUCUAAUGCCACCACUGAUCUGAUAGGAGGUGGAACUCAGGUGGUAAUUCAAGCCAUGGGGAGCUGCUGUAAAUACAGAUGAAGCUGCUCAUCUCCUGUUGUGUGGCCCAGUUCCUAGCAGGCCACAGACUGGGAUGGGUCCACAGCCCGGGGGUUGGGGACCCCUGGCCUAGGACAUUACUGUACACUACUAUAGACUCUAUAACACUGUACACCUAGGCUACACUAAAUUUGCUUUACAAAUGUUUCUUUCUUCAAUGAUAAAUUAACCUUAGCUUACUCUGUUUUUACUUUAUAAACUUUUUAAUUUUUUCAACUUUUGACUCUUUUGUAGUAACACUCAGCUUAAAACACAAACACAUUGUACGGCUGUACAAAAAAUGUUUUCUUCUUUAGAUCCUUAUUUUAUAAGCUUUUAAAAAUUUUAAUUCUUAAACUUUUUUUGUUAAAAACAAAGACACAAGCACACACACGAGCCUAGACCUAUCACUGUCUUCCACCUCCACAUCUUGUCCCACUGGAAGGUCUUCAGGGGCGAUAACGUGCAUGGAGCUGCCAUCUCCUAUGAUAACAAUCGGGAAUACCUACUGAAGGACCUGCCUGAGGCUGUGUUACACUGAACUUUUUUCUUUUCUUUUUUUUUUUUUUUUUAAUAAGUAGGAGUACACACGGCCCAGGCCAGGUACAGUGGCUCACCUGGCUCACUCUUGUAAUCCCAGCACGUUGAGAGGGUGAGGCAGGCAGAUUGCUUGAGCCCAGGAGUUUGAGACCAGCCUGGGAAACAUAGUGAAACCCCUUCUCUACAAAAAAAUACAAAAAUUAUCCAGGCAUGGUUGUGCAUACCUGUAGCCCCUGCUACUCAGGAGGCUGAGGUGGGAGGAUGGCUUGAGCCGGGGAGGUCAAGGCUGUCCAAUAUCAAGGAUUCCUGAUAUUUGCAAGUGAGCCCAAAGGUGUUUAACCCAUGAGUGAGCCAUGAUCGUGUUACUGUACUCCAGCCUGGGCAACAGAGUAAGACCCUGUCUCAAAAAAAUUAAAAAUAAAAAGUAGGAGUAUAUUCUAAAAUAAUGGUAAAAAUAAUAUUGUAAAUAUAUAAACCUAAAACAUAGUCUUUUAUUAUCAUUAUCAAGUAUUAUGUUGUGGGCCUAAUUGUAUGUGCUGUGCUUUUGUAUAACUGGUAAAGCAAGCUAGUUUACACCAGCCUCACCACCAGCAUUUGAGUGUUGCAUUGCGCUAUGAUGUUAUGACAGCUAUGGUGUCACUAGGCAAUAGGAAUUUUUCAGCUCCAUUAGAGUCUGAUGGGACUUAUAUGUCUUAUAUGUGGUCUGUAGCUGACCAACUAAAACAUCAUCAUGCUGUGCAUGACUGUAAUUAAUGGCUGUCCUUCAACUCCUUAGCUGGGCACUAAGGUUCUCCACCACAAGCUGACCUUUCCAUCCUCCCUCCUCUACCCAUGGGCUCAUUUGAAGGUGUGUUACCUCUGUGUUUUGCUCUAGCUGUGCCCUGACUUGGCUCCUCUUCCUUCCUUUCUGCUUAUGGAAAUCUUUUUGGAACUCCCCUGCUCUGCUGCUCCGUCCCCCACACUGUCCUUUUAUGUUUCGUGUGUCUGAACUUGUCUCUCUUCUAGGCUGUUAGCUCUUUAAGAGUCAGGAUUGCCAGCUGGGUCCAGCUGUUAUUUGAGCAAAUCCUCCUUGUUUCCGGGCGUCAGUUUCCUCUUCUGUAUAGUAAAGUGUUGUUAAAUCAGUUGUUCUCCACACUACCCUUCAGUGGUUUCUUUUUUUUUUUUUUUCUUUGAGAUGGUCUCACUCUGUUGCCCAGGCCGGAGUGCAGUGGCGUGAUCUCGGCCCACUGCAGCCUCUGCCUCUUGGUUUCAAGCGAUUCUUUGCCCCAGCCUCCCAAGUAGCUGGGAUUAUAGGUGUGUGCCACCACGCCUGGCUAAUUUUUGUCUUUUUAGUAAAGACGGGGUUUCACCAUGUUGGUCAGGCUGGUGUUGAACUCCUGACUCAGGUGAUCCACCCGCCUCGGCCUCCCAAAGUGCUGGGAUUACAGGCGUGAGCCACCACGCCUGGCCCUUCUAGUGGUUUCUGUUGACUUCUACCCACAACACCUCGCCUGUGACCCAAGCCAUCUGGACAGAAGUGAUCCUAGGUCAGCUGCUCAGUGGUAUGGUAGGUUUGGUAAGAGUGGGAAGGGUGCAGCACAGCCCCAUCCCCGCUGUUGGGGUCAGAAGGGCAAUGUUCCCAGCAUCGGGGCUAGACUAAGAACACAGGGACCUUGGCUGAUUACUGUCCAUUUCUCCAGGACCUGGCAUGUGGUAGUGCAAAUUAAAUGUUGCACAAUUGAAUGUCGGCAGCCAAAGACACCCUGCCUGGCUCCUGGGGGGCUCCCAGCUUAAAGUUCAGAUACUGUAUUAGGUCCGAGACUUGCCCUAGUAUCUGGGCGUUUUACACAAACUCUGGUUAGACACUUAAAUGCAUUAUCUCUUUUAAUCCUAACAAUAACCUUUUUAUUAUUUCUCUUACAGAUCAGGAAAUUGAAGGCCAGAAGGGUAAAGUGGUUUGCCCAAGGCCAUGGGGCUGGUGUGUGGCUGAGUUGUGGCUUGAGCUAAGGGCUUGUAAGAGUUGACAGUCAGUAUUCCGAGAGGGAGAUGUAGGUGGAGACAGGAGAUGAAGCUGAAAGAUGAGAGACAGUCAGCCAGAGAGAAUGGAAGGAAAGAACAGGAAAGCAGAGAGAGGAGUGUCUGCCAGUCCCAGGAUACCACGGCUAUAUCAGCUUUCUAUUACUACCUAACAAAUGAUCACAAACUUUGAUACUCAAAGUCACACACAUUUAUCAUUUUUUAGUUUCUGUACGUCAGAAGUCAAGGCACAACUUAGCAGAGUUCUCUGCUUCAGGUCUUGCCAGGCUGGGCUGCAGUCGGGAGUUGGCCAGGGCUGUGGUCUCAUCCCAGGCUUGACGGGAAAGAUCUGCUUCCAAGGUCGUCAGGUUGCUGAGACCUGAAUUCACCUCCUAUGGUUGUUGGACUGAAGUCCUGUUCUCUUGCUGAUUGUUGGCCGGGGGUCACUCUCAGCAAUUAGAGGUUGCCCGCAGUCCUUUGCUACUUGACCCUCUCGUUAGGCCCAUGAGUGUCUCUAAUAAGACAGAGCCUUUUAUAUACUAUAACCGAAUUACAGAAGUCACAUUACCUUCACCAUAUAACUUAACCUAAUCUCAGGAGUAACAUUGUAUAACCUUUGCUGUAUACUAUUGCUUAGAAGCAAUUCACAGGUCCCACCCACAUGCAAGGGAGGGGAUUAUUCAGGAUGUAAACAUGAGGGCCACUCUGGGGACCUUGGAUCUAGACUGCUCUGAAGUUUGUGGGGGUCAGGGUCCUUGACUCCUCCUGAUCUGGCAUCUCUCUAUCCACUGCAGUCUCCCUUCUCCAGAGUUGCCCCAUUUUCUCUCCUGGAGCACUGGAGCUGGAAGCGACCUUAUGGCCAUCUGCACACCUCUCUGGAGCCUCCAGACCUGCUGGGCUCUAAGAGCUCUUUGCAGGUUUCUGGGGAGGCUAAGGAAGUCCAGUUUGCCUGAAUGUUACAGUUCUUUGCCCCUAGCCAUAGUUCUGUAAUUCCUGGCUGAACACCCUGUCCCUUGAGAGCCCAGAAACUUUCAUUGGCCUUUCUGUGUCUCUGAUCAGCUUAAACUGAGAAUGCCAACUUCAUAAACACUGCUUGUUUACAGACAAAGCUGAGGACCCUGGGAGAUAAUAAUAAGGGGUCUUUGAAGGCCAAAGGAUUGGGAAACACUCCUCUGGGCACCUGCUGGAUUUCAGCCCUGGGAAGACCUGAAAUGUCCAUCCUGAUUUUUCGUAGGAGGAGAAACAGCCUAGAAGGGAUGAUAAGGGUGUGAGCUCCUUCCCAGAGCCCAUCUCUCUUCCCCACACCCUGACUAGAUGGCGGGGGUGAAUUGGGGCCAGAGUGGGUGCAAGAGUCAGAUUGGGGGGGCCUUAUGGUCGGUAUUAAGGAGUUGAACUUUAUUUUGAGGAAAAGAAGGGGGAAGGGGAGGGACGUGGUCGGAUUGGGGUAAGAAAGAUGACUGUGACCCAAAUGUGGGAACGAAUGUGUGUGUGCUGGGAGGGAGCAAGACUGAGGACUCGAGGGCCAGGUGGGUGAUCCGAGGGAUGCAGGAAAGAGCCUAUGCCAGAUUAAUGGCUGUGAGAAGCGGUGUGAGCUGAGAGGCCUGAGAUCUCUUUAAGAGGUUGGAUUAGCAGGCCUUAGUGACUGAGUGCAUUUUGUAGGUGAGGUAAGAGCGAGGUGACAGGAUCAACUUCUGAGUUGAUAGCAAGGUCAUUGGCUCAUCAAUGGAGCAGGACAUACCAGUUGAGAUAUCAAGUAGGCAUUUGGCUAUUCAGGCCUGGGGUGCACAGGAGAGCUCUGGGCUCCUGGGCACACACGGGAGCCCUGGGUGUACAGGAGGCAGGCGUGUGUUAGCUGUGGAAGGGAGGUCCCUCCUGCCUCAGCUUAUCCUGCUCUCCCUCUGCCUGAACUCCUCCAGUUCUGGAAGGCACCCUGCAGUCCCACACCUGGGCCCUCUUCUCUGCCACUCCCUCUGCCUGCAACAGGCUUCUCUCCUGGACUGCCCCCUUCCCUGCACCUUGCCAACAUGCAUGCACACACACAGGCACUCAUGCACACGCUCACAUAUGCACCCAUGCAUGCACACUUACAUGCACACAUGCACUCUUACAUCUUUUGCCUGGCCAAUUCCUACUCUCCUGUCAGCUCUCAGCUUAAAGGCCACUGCCUCCUCUGAUAACUCAUUGCUGACCUUCUAUACUAGGGCUCCCCUCUGCCCACUGGAGGCCCCUUACUUGUUUGUCCUUUUUCUCCAAGUUCUCCUCACAAAUAGUAAUUAUUUAAUGUCUGUCUUCCCCACUAGGCUGUAGGUUCCAUGAGGACAGGCCUUGAGUCUGUCCUGGUCUCUGGAAUCACGGUGUCUAGUAGAGGCCAGCACACAGCAAAUAUAUAAAUGUACAAAUGAGUGAAUGAAGAGAAUCUGAUUGGCCUUAAGGAACUUACGCACUUAAAAUAAUUGGGCAGAAGAGAAGCAGUGAAGGAGUGCAGAGGCAUCACCUGAAAGUUUACAAGUCCUUCCACUUUCUCUCUGAGGCAGAAAGAGCAAGGGUUUUUCUCUCCAUUUUAUGGUUGGGAAAAUUGAGGCCUGCCUGAGUGUGUGACUUGUGGCAAGUCACUCUGGUCAUCUAGGGCAGAGGCUCCCCAGAUCCCAGGCCUCCUGCCUCCAGUCCCCAGCCCGCAGCCCAGGAUUAGGCAGAGCCAGCUGCUUUCCCGUGGCUGCCCUGACUCCUUACAGGGAUCACUGAGAUUCUGAUGAACAGACCUUCUGCCCGCAAUGCCUUGGGGAAUGUCUUCGUCAGUGAGCUGCUGGAAACUCUGGCCCAGCUGCGGGAGGACCGGCAAGUGCGUGUCCUGCUCUUCAGAAGUGGAGUGAAGGGCGUGUUCUGUGCAGGUGCAGACCUGAAGGAGCGGGAACAGAUGAGUGAAGCAGAGGUGGGGGUGUUUGUCCAGCGACUCCGGGGCCUGAUGAAUGACAUCGCAGCCUUCCCUGCACCCACCAUUGCGGCUAUGGAUGGGUUUGCCUUGGGCGGAGGCCUAGAGCUUGCCCUGGCCUGUGACCUCCGAGUGGCAGCUUCCUCGGCAGUCAUGGGACUGAUUGAGACCACGCGAGGGCUCCUCCCGGGGGCAGGAGGGACUCAGAGGCUGCCCCGUUGUCUGGGGGUGGCCCUGGCGAAGGAGCUCAUCUUCACGGGCCGACGACUGAGUGGAACUGAGGCCCACGUACUGGGGCUGGUGAAUCACGCUGUGGCCCAGAACGAGGAGGGGGACGCCGCCUACCAGCGGGCACGAGCACUGGCCCAGGAGAUCCUGCCCCAGGCCCCCAUUGCCGUGCGGCUGGGCAAAGUAGCCAUUGACCGAGGAACGGAGGUGGACAUUGCAUCUGGGAUGGCCAUUGAAGGGAUGUGCUAUGCCCAGAAUAUUCCAACCCGGGACCGGCUAGAGGGCAUGGCAGCCUUCAGGGAGAAGCGGACUCCCAAAUUUGUUGGCAAAUGACCCCCAUUUUAACCUUCAGCAUGGGAGAUGCAUGCCCUGAAGAGCAGGAUCCAGAAGGAAGAUUUGUGGCCAGAUUGCCUUCAUCAUUUCACCUCUCCAGACUUCCAUUUCUUCACAAGGAUGAUGAUGGAAAUAAAAUGACUGGCGUGAUGCCUGGAACCAAGGUGCUGAUCCUACCACCUACUGCUACCUUCCUUAGCUUCACCCUGGCUAGAAAUAAUCACGAGGGUUGGGUUUGCUUUGGAAAAUGCCUGUCUCUCUACUUGAAUGAUAAAGAAUUAAAUUAGAUCUCUCUGAGUCUUGGUAUCAUUGGCUCUCAGCCCCUGACCUCUCUCAGUUAUCAGGCACUCAUUAGAGAUGUCAGAAGAUUUUAAGAUACCCCUAGUUUCUUCCUGUGAACAACAGAGGUAAUAAAUAAACUCUGACAUCGGUUGAACAUGUGUCAGGGGUCAGACUGCAGAUCCCAGUCUCUGCCAGUUACUUGCUGUAUAACCGUGGACAAAUUGUUUAAAUGCUCUGGGCCUCAGCUUCCUCACCUACAAAACAAAACUUGUGAAGAUUUAGCAAAAUAAAAACACUUCAUAUUCAAUAAAUAUGUUUUAAUUGUUAA